GGGGGCCCGAAGCGCCAGAGAUGGCUGCUCAGCGAGGGAUGCCCAGCUCCGCCGUGAGGGUCCUGGAAGAGGCGUUGGGCAUGGGUUUGACGGCAGCCGGGGACGCGAGGGACACGGCGGACGCGGUGGCGGCUGAGGGCGCCUACUACCUGGAACAGGUCACCAUAACUGAAGCAUCUGAAGAUGACUAUGAAUAUGAAGAGAUACCAGAUGACAAUUUUAGCAUCCCAGAAGGUGAAGAAGAUCUGGCAAAAGCAAUUCAGAUGGCCCAAGAACAGGCUACAGAUACUGAAAUUUUGGAACGGAAAACAGUUCUUCCUUCAAAGCAUGCAGUACCUGAAGUAAUAGAAGACUUUCUCUGCAAUUUCUUGAUCAAAAUGGGAAUGACCAGAACUCUUGAUUGCUUUCAGUCUGAAUGGUAUGAGUUAAUACAGAAAGGAGUGACUGAACUUAGAACUGUUGGGAAUGUUCCAGAUGUCUACACCCAGAUUAUGCUUUUGGAAAAUGAGAACAAAAAUUUAAAGAAAGAUUUGAAGCACUACAAACAAGCAGCUGACAAAGCUAGAGAAGAUUUGCUGAAAAUUCAGAAAGAACGUGAUUUUCAUCGAAUGCAUCAUAAGCGAAUAGUCCAGGAAAAAAACAAAUUAAUUAAUGACCUCAAAGGGUUGAAGUUACAUUAUGCAUCUUAUGAACCGACUAUAAGGGUGUUACAUGAGAAACACCACACUUUACUGAAGGAGAAAAUGCUGACCUCCUUGGAAAGAGACAAAGUAGUUGGGCAGAUUUCUGGACUUCAAGAAACAUUGAAGAAACUGCAAAGAGGACAUAGUUACCAUGGUCCUCAAAUUAAAGUUGAUCAUAGUCGUGAAAAAGAAAAUGCACCAGAAGGUCCUACUCAGAAAGGUCUUCGUGAAGCCAGGGAACAAAACAAAUGUAAAACAAAGAUGAAAGGCAAUACAAAGGCCUCCUUCAACAGAAAUCAAGAGAAAGCUUAUGAGCUCAGUGCGAGAACAGCCCUCUGUCUAACUCCAUGCCUCCAUCAGCAGCAGUGGACAGGGAACUCUCAAACUUGGAAUAAGACCGUACCUCUGCAGGACACUAUUGGCAGGAGACAAGAGAACAACAGUGCACACCAGCACAUCGACUAAGACUGCCCAUCUUCAGGACAUUUGUCAGCAGGAGCCAAAUGGGAAAUUCUGAGCAACAGGUGUUCCUGGCUUGUUCUCCUCCAAUCCUCCCUUUCGUCAACACCCAUACCCUUUAUCUGUGUUCUUUACAGUCUUCAUAAAAGGAGUCCAGGACUUCCAGUUAAUCAUUUAUCCCAGAACUCUAAUCCUCCGUAAGGAUCCUUUUUUUUUGACCCAAUAUUUCCCUCUUCUGACUCCCCAAACCCUUUCUUUGUACUCUAUUGAAUUCAAGGUCAGUCAACAAAAAAGUCCUUUAUAUUUUAAUAUUUUACUAUGAGUGUUCCCUUCACCUUCUGUGCUAAUGAAAAUCUAGAUUUUCCUUCAUGAUAGUUUCCCCUGCAUCCAUUGAGGUUCUGGUAAAUGUUUUAACAAUCAACUCUUUGGAAGAAGAAAACAAAAGCCUUGAUUUGUAUAGUGUUUUCCAGUUUCUGUGCUGUUAAACACUCACACCAUAGCCAUUUAAGCUAUCUUCUCACUUCACUGAAUAAGGAGCCUGGGACUUGAUGUCCACACUCAGCUCUCCUAAGCCAGUAUGAGAGAGCAACAACACAUCACAUCUUACAGUACCUUUAAGGGUAACUGUUCUCUCUACUCCACUCAAAUGUAGCAUAGGUCCUGAAAGUCAGAUAAGUGUCCCCUUUGCUUCUCAUUGCUGCUUUCAGUUUGUUCUCCCUCCUUCAUGAACAUACCCUUCCGUGAAUCUCAUGUCAUCAGAUUUGCCCACUCAUUGUACCUUUUUGUUAUGGGCACCUCUUCUCACCUCAUCUUUUUGUCAAUUAAAAAAAUUAAUCCCCGUGAUAUUGUCACUUUCUUAAAAGUGAUUCCUCCAUAAUGCUUCAUGAUUGAAAUGUUGAUAUGGAUGAUCCUUCUAACUCUCUGAAGUUUCAGUUCCUUGACAGCCUCUCCUCCAGUGAUCCACUUAACUCACUUUCAUAGUCAUUUCCUAGGCCUUGUUAUUGCAAGUAACUGCUAUAAUUUUUCAUUGCCUCUAUUGUUUGCUCCCUACCCCCCGAAUCUCUGCAUACUGAGGUGUUUCAAGGCUCAGUUCUUGACCCUCUGUUGGUUGUCUUCACUCCCUAGGUGAUCUCAUCCAGUCUUAUGGCUUUAAAUUCUGCCUAUAUAUUAAUUAUCCCUUAAUUUACAUCUUCAACUGAGAUCUCUUCUCUGAACUCUAGUUUCAUAUAUCCAACUGCUUACUGAACACCUCCAGUUAAAUGUCAUUUCUUCAUUUCAAUUAUCUCCCCUUCCAUGUUCUCCUUCUUAAUUAAUGGAAACUCCACACUUUAGUUACUUAGCCAAAAAACUCUAGAGUCAUCCCUGAGACGUCUCUCUCUCUCACAUCUCACAUCUGAUAAGAAAAAGAAAUUAUUUUGGCUCUAUCUUUGAAAAAAUAUCUACAUUUUCAUUUUUUCUUACCACUAGCACUUUUGCUCUCUGUUUUUUUUUUUUUGCCACCGUCUGUAGUUUGUAUUAUUGCAAAAGCCUCCUAACUGAUCUCUGCUUUUGUCUUUACUUUUCUUCAGUCUCUUUUGAACACAGCAGCCACAGUCAUCUUCUUAAAACAUAAGUCUGUCCAUGACAUUUCUCUGCUGAAAAUUUUCCAGUAACCUCCCAUCUUACUGAGUUACAGGUAAGGUCAUUAUAACCUCUGAGGCCCUACAUUACCUAGAUCCCUUUUACCUCUCUGACAUUAUCUCCUGCUACCCUCCCAUCUUUUGCUCAAUUGCAGGCACACUAGCCUCCUACAAAUUCUACUUAUUUAUAGAACACUGUAGGUAUGCCCCACCUUGAGGCUCUUGCACUUGAGUUUUUAUCUUCUGUCUGUGUUAUUUUCCUUCAGAUAAUUCAGAUGGCUCAUCUCUCACUUUAUUUAAAGCUUUACUCAAAUGUUCCCUUUUCAGAGAGACUUUUCAUAGCCAUCCAAUCUAAAUUUUAAUGCUGCCUCUAAUUCACUGGCACUUCUUUGGCCUCUAUCCUACUUUAAUUUUUCUUUUUGCCUAUCUUACAUAUCUCUCAUAUGCUAUGUUGUACUUAUUAACUCAUUGUAUCACUUCCCACUAGAAUGUAAGUCCCAUGAAAGCAGGAAUAUUUAUUAAUUGUAUUCACUGCUAUAUUCUCAGUGCCAGAAAAAUGCCUGGCAAAUAGUAAUUAUCCCAUAAAUAUGUAAAUUUGAAGGAAUGCAUAAAUUAAAAAAUGUGUUUUGUUAGUUGCUAUUGUAUAGAUAUGCAUUGAUUACUACAAGUUGAUCAGAAAUAGAGUGUUUCUGCUAAACCCCCUGUUUCUAUAAUUUGUCUAUAGGCUUUUUGGGAAUUUUCUUUGUAAGUAGUAUCAUCUGUGAAAAAUAAUAGUUGUGACUUUCAUUUUUCAAUUCUAAAAAUUUUUAUUUGUAUUUCUUAUAUUUGUGCUUUGUCUAGGUCCUCCAGAAAGUUAAAUAGAAGUGGUUAAAUAGUGGUGGUUAUACUAUUUGUGAUUUUAAAGGUGAUGCAUCUGAUGUUUCAACACAAGGAAUGAUAUUUAUUGUCUUUGGUGGUUAUUCUUUAUCAAGUUGAAAAAAUUUGUUUUCCUUUGAUAUUUAAAGUUUGUGUUUUACCAUGAGUAUAUUAAUUUUUUUGACCAUAAGUGAUUGGUAAUUUUAUCAUGUUUAAGUUUUAAGAUUUUAUUUUAUCAUGAAUAAGUAUUGUAUUUUCUGCUUCUGAGACUGUUUUCUCCAUUAAUAUUUUAAUGUGGUAAAUGUUGCCAUGGAUUUUAAAAUGUAAACAUUCUCUUUCAUUCCUGGAAUAAAACUAAUGUAUUCAUCAUGUGUUAUUUGAGUUACAUAACACUGGACCUAGUUAAUCAUUUUUUCAUAGGAUGCUUACUUCUAGUUUAUGAAUAAAAUUGAUCUUUAAUUUUCCUGUUCAGUCACUGUCUUUUUAUAAUUUUAGUAUCAUUGAAUAAGUUGUGGAAUAGUUCCUUUCUUCUAUUCUUUGAAAGAUUUUUAUACCCUGGAAGACCUAUUCCUUAAAUGUAUGGUAGAAGUCUUCUGUAAAACUAAUUGGAACUGUUAUAUAUUUAUAGGAAGAUUUUAUACUGUGGAUUCAGAUUUCUUUGUAAUGUAAUAGAAGUUAUUUCUUCCUUAAUCAAUUUUUAUAAAUUCUGAAGUAAUAUGCUUACAUGAAUAUGACCAUUUCAUCUGAGUUUUAAAUUUACUGGCUUAAAAUAUUUAUCAUAUUUUUUAUUAUCUUUUAAAUCUCAAAUGGAUCCAUAAUUAUAUUCUCUUUAAUUUGUGAAUUCUAUUUCUUGCCCUCCCUUCCAACAGUUUUCCCCUCCCUUCCCAUCUCACAUCAUUCUUCCUGUAAAUAUAUAAAUUUUGUUGGUACUUUUAAAGAUCCAAGCUUUGGAUUUUAUAAUCAUUAUGUUUAGCUUUUUUCUUGUAUAACUUUGUAGUUUCAUUGUUAUGAUCUUCUUCUGCCUAUAGUCUUUGAGUUUAUGCUUUGUUUCUUUUUCCAGCUUCUUAAGUUGAUACAUAACUCAUUAAUGGUUGGCUUUUCUACUAUUUUAAGUACUUAAUACUAUUAAUUUUCCCCAAAUACUGUUUCAACUGCAUCCCACAGAUGUUUAUAUGUAGCAUUUUAAUUUUUGUUUAGUUUUAAGUAUUUUAAGGUUUCCAUUAUGGUUUGUUCUUUGUCCUGUGGCUUAUGUAGAGGACAUUUUCAAAUUUACAUAUGCAUGGGUUUUGGGUUAUUUUUUUAUUUGGGUUAUUAUGUAUUUGUAGUUGAAAUAAAUCAUGGUCAGAAUGCAUGGUUUGUAUGAAACCAAUUCUUGAAAUUUCUUGGGAGUUGCUAUGGCAGAGAUUUCUAGUUUUCUACCAAAAAAUGUUUUCUUUAUUCCUGUAGUUUUCAUGAUAUAGCUGGGCAUAUAGUUAGGUACCUGUAUUUUUCAGUAUCCUGUACACCUAGAUGUUACCAUGAAACUAAAUGUUGCCAGUGGAAUUUGCACUUAAUAGUUGUGUGUUUGUGGAAUUACCUUUCAGAAAUAUUUACUCCCUCCCAUCAUUUUAAAGAAAGGAUUCUACUUCCCUGAUUUUUUUAGUCUUUGUUUUUUUCUUUUUUUUGAGACAGGGUGUCACUCUGUCACCCAGGCUAGAGCUCAGUGGCAUGAUCGCGGCUCACAGUAGCCUCGACCUCCCAGGGCUCAGCUGAUCCUCCCACCUCAGCCUUCCAAGUAGCUGGGACUACAGGCCUGCACCACCACACCUGGCUAAUUUUUAUAUUUUUUUGUCAAGAUAGAGUUUUGUCAUGUUGCUCAGGCUGGUCACAAACUCCUGGACUCAAGAGAUCUGUCUGUCUUGGCCUCCCAAAGUGCUGAGAUUACAGGUGUGAGCCACUGCACCCAGCUGUUUCCUGAUUAUUGAUGUAGAGCUUGGCCUUGGCCAUGUAACUUAUUUUGGUCAAUGAUAAUUUGAGAAACCUGACUCUACAGAAGCUUGAUAUAUGCUUGCACAUUUAGGUUUGCUCUGUCUGCCAUGGGCAUGAAAAGAAUGCGGCCAUUUCCCUUGAUAAUAUAUGUUCUUCAGAAACAUUAGAUAAUGUCAUAAUGCAUUAUUACUUGGAUAUUUCACAAUGUAUUUUAUGUUCCCAUGUCUACUCAUUUUGUUUAUUUCCGUUGUUUUGCUGUUUCAAAUAAUUCUAUGAGGCAAUUCUUAUACAUUAAAUUCUGUUCAUAUCUUAUUGUUUCUUUGGUAUAAAACUCAAGAACUGGUGAUCUUGGAUUAAAGGAUAUAAACAAG